AGUGAGUGAGCGAGCGAGCGCCGCGCGCGCCGCCGCUGCCACCUCCGCUGCUCGGCCCGGUCCCGGAGUGGCCCGGCCGGCCCGCGGGGCGCGGAGCCGAGGCCCGCGGCUGGCUGCAUGAAGGACUGCGAGUACCAGCAGAUCAGCCCCGGGGCCGCCCCGCUGCCCGCCUCCCCGGGGGCGCGCCGUCCCGGCCCCGCCGCGUCCCCGACUCCGGGCCCCGGGCCCGCGCCGCCCGCCGCCCCCGCCCCGCCGCGCUGGAGCAGCAGCGGCAGCGGCAGCGGCAGCGGGAGCGGGAGCCUCGGCCGCCGCCCACGGCGCAAGUGGGAGGUGUUCCCGGGUCGCAAUCGCUUCUACUGCGGCGGCCGCCUCAUGCUGGCCGGCCACGGCGGCGUCUUCGCGCUCACGCUGCUGCUCAUCCUCACCACCACCGGCCUCUUCUUCGUCUUUGACUGUCCCUACCUGGCUCGCAAGCUGACCCUUGCCAUCCCCAUCAUCGCUGCCAUCCUCUUCUUCUUCGUCAUGAGCUGCCUGCUGCAGACAAGCUUCACCGACCCUGGGAUCCUGCCCCGGGCCACUGUCUGUGAAGCAGCCGCCCUGGAGAAACAGAUCGACAACACAGGCAGUUCUACAUACCGGCCACCCCCUCGGACCCGGGAGGUGCUGAUCAACGGGCAGAUGGUGAAGCUGAAGUACUGCUUCACCUGCAAGAUGUUCCGGCCACCCCGAACCUCACACUGCAGUGUCUGCGACAACUGUGUGGAACGAUUUGACCAUCACUGCCCCUGGGUGGGCAACUGUGUGGGGAGACGGAACUAUCGCUUCUUCUACGCGUUUAUUCUCUCCCUCUCAUUCCUGACGGCCUUCAUCUUCGCCUGUGUGGUCACCCACCUGACGUUGCGCGCUCAGGGAAGCAACUUCCUCUCCACUCUGAAGGAGACACCAGCAAGCGUGCUGGAGUUGGUGAUCUGCUUCUUCUCCAUCUGGUCCAUUCUGGGCCUCUCAGGGUUUCACACGUACCUCGUCGCCUCCAACCUGACUACUAAUGAAGACAUCAAAGGCUCGUGGUCCAGCAAGAGGGGCGGUGAGGCCUCUGUCAACCCCUACAGCCAUAAAAGUAUUAUCACCAACUGCUGUGCUGUGCUCUGUGGCCCCCUACCUCCCAGCCUAAUUGACCGGAGGGGAUUUGUGCAGUCCGACACCGUGUUGCCCUCACCCAUCAGAAGCGAUGAGCCAGCCUGCAGAGCCAAGCCUGAUGCCAGCAUGGUAGGAGGCCACCCCUGACCACGGCUCAGUACUUGCCACCUGCUGGCCUGUCUGACCCUCCGCACUCACCUGCCGGGACCCUCCCUAUUCCAUCCAAGGGAAGCAGAACUGCCAAAGACUCAAGUCUUUUCAUAUUUAUUUCCCAUCCUGCGUGGCUUUCCCUGAACUGUUCCGUGGCUGUGCCCUCUGCUCCCCAAACCCAGGUUCCCACAGCCUUGGGCCCUAGGUACCCCAGCUGAUCAGUGCCAGGAGAGACCAGAGCCUCUGGAGGCUACCCAGGGGACCACACCAAGUCCUUGCCUGUGCCGGGCGAGCCCUGUGUGAGUGAGGCUGUGAACUGAGCGUGAGGCCUCCCAGGUGGGGGAACUGCUUGGGCCUUGCUGAGCCAGGGUCCUCAGGGUGAAGCAGGACUGAGGAGUGGCCAGCUCUGGAUAGCUGGCUGUGGAGAGGAAGCCUCCAUGGGCUGCUUUGGUCUGUGGGCUCCUUCAUUCCCUUGGUGAUAAUUUCCCUUUAUUCUGUGGGAUUUUUGGUGGGGUUUUCCCCCCUUUUUUAUGGAGUUGGCCAAUAGGAUUGAGUUGGGGCUCCAGUAGAGAAGGCAGGGUUGGUGGUGGGUGGGGGCAGCCUGUAUCAGACAAAGGUAAAUCAGCCAGCCAGGCACCCACAGCCUCAGCUCCUGUGCAGUUCCUGGGCAGCACAGUGGAAGUGGGAGCCUGGUCCUUCCCCUGCCCAUGGAGAGCUCUUUAAGGGAUCCCAGCCUGCCCCUCCACUUCUCUCCCAAGCCAGGUCCCGGCAUGGGUGGGUUAUGCUCAUGCUGGCAAUACUUGAAACGGGUUUAUUAAUGCUGGGUAUUUUGCACAAUUUUAUAGACCUCUUUUCUACAUAGUCUUUUUUAAAUGGAAGGAGAAAAUGUCAGCCACAUUACUGUCUGUGUAGUGCCAGGUGAAGGGUUAUCAGAAGGCUGGUUGGUUUUAAUAAGUUUAUUCCAAGAGACCUUCUGGCUGGAAUGAGUGAGAGUGUGUGUGCAUGUGUGUGUGUGUUCAUGUGUGCCCUGUAUGAAUGUGGCUGGCUCCCAUAUCCCCUGGGCUGCCCCCUGCCCCAUCCCCUUUGAGUGUCAGAAGCACUCUGAGCCAAGGGGACAGGGGGCACGUGCACUGGUCACGAGAAAACCCUGGGCUCCCACUGGGGCUCAGCCCAGCCUCCUAUCUUUCCUUCUUCUAUGGACUUCAGACAGCCAGUGUCUGGGGACUCUGCCACUCUACCCCCAGCCCUACCCACCAGCCCCCAGGUGAGGCUUCCAGCUGGGACCUGCCCAGACAGGCUGAGCCUGGGCGUGGUGGGUGGGGUGAUGGCUCUGGGGAGCGGCUGCCAUCCUACAAGCCACACCCCCUCCUCUGAGCUCUGAAUAUGGGACCCAGUGCCAGGAGCUGGAAGACAAGGUGUUUCUGCCAAACGGGGACCUCCAUCCAGAGAAAAGGAAGAAGGUGCAGGGUGGGCCAAGAGGCAAGUGAAGGUUGGCCUGAGUCUGGGCCGGAAACUCAGAGGAUGUUUCUCCUCUGCUGGGAGCUGUAGUUUCUUAUCAAAAUAGAUAUUGUUCCACCAUCCCCCUCCUUGGCCCUUCAAGUGGGCUGAAGCCCUUGGAAAGUGACAUAGGAAGUCCCCAGAUCUUGCCCUUCUCACUCCAGAGGCUAGUGGUCACAGACAGCUGGGAAUGGCAGCCACAGAGGGUCCCCUCUGGGAGAAACAGCUUCACCCCAGCCUCAGGGCCCUGGGCCAUCACUGCAGUGGCCCUGGGAGGUGAGGAAGAAGCUGGCUAGAGGAGGGGGCUCCCACCUACCUUUUAUUUAAGCCAGUAUUCUUUGUUCCUGCUUGUAAUAAAACUUCAGUUUAUAAGAGUUGCUUUGCUUUGGUUUGGUUUUUGUUUGCUUUUCCUUUGCUGAGGCCCCAACUGGGAGCCCUCUGUUCUUUCAGACAAAUUUGGUUCUUUCCUGGGGAGACUGUGAGAAGGCAGGCAGCCCAGUGAUCUGGCUACAUUUUCCCUCACCUGGCUGGAGCUCUGUCCGCUGGAGGAAGAGCAGAGAGGGCUGCGGCUGAGCCCCCAUGGGCACGUGAAAAGAGGCCAUCCUGUCCCCUCUUUGUCCCCUCCACCUUCCCCUGCCUCAGGGGCUUGGAGACCCCCAAAUUCUUCUUCCCUACUGCCUUUCCACUCCGAUCCCCAAUGAGUGCCCAGCUAAGAAAAUGUUUGAGACAGUAGAUUCCAGUUUGAGAGCCGGAGCUUCCCUGGCUACCACCUCCAACCUGGGCACCAGGGCCCAGCCAGACAACUCAUAACACUGGCCCACCUCUCUGGUAUCUCCCUCAGGAGGACACCUGUCAGGAUUUUGCCAUCUCCUGCACAGCCUGAGGGGAGCUAACAGGCCUCUUUGCAGAGGGUUAGCUGGUAAGACCGUUUCUUCCCUGUCGGCCAGCACUGCCCGCUCCCCUCACACACCAUCUCAUCCUCAUCGCAUGCCUCGCCAACCCCAUGGAGCCCGUCCAUCUGUCUGGUGUGUGGUGCGGUGUGUGUGCUGGUGGUGGUAGGGUCUCCAGGGACUCCCCGCUAAGCAGAAGGAUCGGGAUAUAGGGCAAGGCUAAAAGCCCAGCCCCAUUGUGGACUGAGGAAGUAGCUUCUCGCAGAGCAGCUCUCCAGCUGGAAGAGGAGGUGGAGGGUGAGGCUGGGGAGAGGAUGGCGAACCUGCCCUGAGGUGCUUGGGUCUGUGCUGGUGGGGUCCUGGUAUGCAGGGGCCACCGGUCACUAACACUCUUAUGUCCUGGCUUUCUGUCCCCGCUGAGCUUUCUCUCACCCGCCCGUUUUCUCUCCUGCUUCAUUGCCUGCUGCCUAAGCCUUGGCCCUUCUCUCGGGCAGAGGCAGGUGCUGUGGCAGCACCUCUCCCCACCACCGGGGCCCCUGCAGGCCGCCUCCCUCCUCCCAGGCCUGCUAACCCUCUCUCUUCUCCUUCUUUGCUGUCCUGCCGGGGAUCUCCAGUGUGUGCGGGGGCUUAAGGACCUCCUGAGGACCGCUGCUCUCUGCCUCUCCAGGAAUGGCCUGGGGGGAGCCAGGCACCCGGCACCUCCACCUGCCUAACCUGUGGCCCAUCUGCCACCAUCUGUGCCUACAGGGUCUGCCCCCCAGCCUGCCCGGCCUGUGUGCUCUCUAGGACCCCCAUAGGGGGCAGGGGCUGGCCUCUUUGCCCCAUUCCCGCUCCAUGCCGGCCAGAGUGUAGAAAGCCAUAACGCAGCCAUCAGCACAAUAAUGUGACUCUACGCUGAUAUGCUCCCUCUCUCCUCCACUGACUUCCCCUUCCCGGAUUUGUGAGGUGUCAAGACUAGGAAUCUGGCCUUAGAGCCUGCCCCUCCACCCCCUCAGAUCAGGCAUAGCCAUAGUCAAGCCCAGCAGGUUUCCUCAGGAGCUGUCUGGGGUGUUGAUGGUGGAUGACGCUGCUGAACAAGUUUGGUGACUGUUCUAAGCACAACUGGCUUGAUACUGUUCCCACGGCCUGUCCACCUCCCACCCCCAACCCUCCACCAGAGUAGGUAGGAUGUAGGGAGGGUGCGUGCCUCCUUUGCUCUAGGCACUGAGGGACCAAGCUAGCCGUGCACAGCCCCAUACACUUCAGGGGACUAAAGGAAAGAGCUGAGCCAAGGAAAAUCAGCUGAGCCCAGGGCUGGGGGCUGCUUGUCUGCUAUCCUGUACCUUUUUUUUUUUUAACCAAAAUAAAGAUUCCCCUCUUCUUGCCAUACCA